CUUAGACACUUCCAGCUGGUGGCAGGGGAUACAGCCAUAAUACAGCUUCCUCUGUCCCAGCUGUCUUCUUCACUACGGUAAAUGCAUUACGAUGGCUGCACUCUCCUGUAAAGGUUCAGGUAGAGGAAGGUGUAGGAUGAAGUCCGGACACCAUCAUUUGGGUUUUUAAAAGCUUCAGCUUCUCCAGCAUCUUUGCAUUGUGAAUAUCUUCCUGCUUCUAGUCAAAGCUUUCUCUCUAGUGAUUGGAAUGCUGCUGUAAGCCUGAUUAGAGGUGCCUGAGGAUAUCACCUUUUACAAGGAAGCCGUGUGUGCUUGAGAGGAUCUUUUUAAAUGCAUUAUGGCUCAUGCAGCCUCACAAUUAAAGAAAAACAGGGAUUUAGAAAUCAAUGCUGAAGAAGAGCCUGAGAAAAAAAGGAAACACCGCAAACGGUCCCGGGAUCGGAAGAAAAAGUCUGAUGCCAAUGCAAGUUACUUAAGAGCAGCUCGAGCUGGACACCUUGAAAAGGCCCUCGACUACAUAAAAAAUGGAGUUGACAUCAACAUUUGCAAUCAGAAUGGGUUGAACGCUCUCCACCUUGCUUCCAAAGAAGGCCAUGUAGAGGUUGUUUCUGAGCUGCUGCAGAGAGAAGCCAAUGUGGAUGCAGCUACAAAGAAAGGAAACACAGCAUUGCACAUCGCAUCUUUGGCUGGGCAAGCAGAGGUGGUAAAAGUCUUGGUUACAAAUGGAGCCAAUGUCAAUGCACAAUCUCAGAAUGGUUUCACGCCAUUGUAUAUGGCAGCCCAGGAAAAUCACCUGGAAGUUGUCAAGUUUCUUCUUGACAAUGGUGCAAGCCAGAGCCUAGCCACAGAGGAUGGCUUCACACCAUUGGCAGUGGCUUUGCAACAAGGUCACGACCAAGUCGUUUCGCUCCUGCUAGAGAAUGACACCAAAGGAAAAGUGCGUCUCCCAGCUCUUCAUAUCGCGGCCCGAAAAGACGACACGAAAGCCGCCGCCCUGCUGCUGCAGAAUGACAACAAUGCAGAUGUGGAAUCAAAGAGUGGCUUCACUCCGCUCCACAUAGCUGCUCACUAUGGAAAUAUCAAUGUAGCCACGUUGCUGUUAAACCGAGCGGCUGCUGUGGAUUUCACCGCAAGGAAUGACAUCACUCCUUUACAUGUUGCAUCAAAAAGAGGAAAUGCAAAUAUGGUAAAACUAUUGCUCGAUCGAGGAGCUAAAAUCGAUGCCAAAACCAGGGAUGGUCUGACACCACUGCACUGUGGAGCAAGGAGUGGCCACGAGCAGGUGGUAGAAAUGUUGCUUGAUCGAGCUGCCCCCAUUCUUUCAAAAACCAAGAAUGGAUUAUCUCCAUUGCACAUGGCCACACAAGGGGAUCAUUUAAACUGCGUCCAGCUUCUCCUCCAGCAUAAUGUACCCGUGGAUGAUGUCACCAAUGACUACCUGACUGCCCUACACGUGGCUGCCCACUGUGGCCAUUACAAAGUUGCCAAGGUUCUCUUGGAUAAGAAAGCUAACCCCAAUGCCAAAGCCCUGAAUGGCUUUACCCCUCUUCAUAUUGCCUGCAAGAAGAAUCGAAUUAAAGUAAUGGAACUCCUUCUGAAACACGGUGCAUCCAUCCAAGCUGUAACCGAGUCGGGCCUUACCCCAAUCCAUGUUGCUGCCUUCAUGGGGCAUGUAAAUAUUGUAUCACAACUAAUGCAUCAUGGAGCCUCACCAAACACCACCAAUGUGAGAGGAGAAACAGCACUGCACAUGGCAGCUCGCUCCGGCCAAGCUGAAGUUGUGCGGUAUCUGGUACAAGACGGAGCUCAGGUAGAAGCUAAAGCUAAGGAUGACCAAACACCACUCCACAUUUCAGCCCGACUGGGGAAAGCAGACAUAGUACAACAGCUGUUGCAGCAAGGGGCAUCUCCAAAUGCAGCCACAACUUCUGGGUACACCCCACUUCACCUUUCCGCCCGAGAGGGGCAUGAGGAUGUGGCCGCGUUCCUUUUGGAUCAUGGAGCGUCUUUAUCUAUAACAACAAAGAAAGGAUUUACUCCUCUUCAUGUGGCAGCAAAAUAUGGAAAGCUUGAAGUCGCCAAUCUCCUGCUACAGAAAAGUGCAUCUCCAGAUGCUGCUGGGAAGAGCGGGCUAACACCACUGCAUGUAGCUGCACAUUACGAUAAUCAGAAAGUGGCCCUUCUGCUUUUGGACCAAGGAGCCUCACCUCACGCAGCCGCAAAGAAUGGUUAUACGCCACUGCACAUCGCUGCCAAAAAGAACCAGAUGGACAUAGCGACAACUCUGCUGGAAUAUGGUGCUGAUGCCAACGCAGUUACCCGGCAAGGAAUUGCUUCCGUCCAUCUCGCAGCUCAGGAAGGGCACGUGGACAUGGUGUCGCUGCUCCUCGGUAGAAAUGCGAAUGUGAACCUGAGCAAUAAGAGCGGCCUGACCCCACUCCAUUUGGCUGCUCAAGAAGAUCGAGUGAAUGUGGCAGAAGUCCUCGUAAACCAAGGGGCUCAUGUGGACGCCCAGACAAAGAUGGGAUACACACCACUGCAUGUGGGCUGCCACUAUGGAAAUAUCAAGAUUGUUAAUUUCCUGCUCCAGCAUUCUGCAAAAGUUAAUGCCAAAACAAAGAAUGGGUAUACGCCAUUACAUCAAGCAGCACAGCAGGGGCAUACGCAUAUAAUAAAUGUCUUACUUCAGAACAACGCCUCCCCCAAUGAACUCACUGUGAAUGGGAAUACUGCCCUUGGCAUUGCCCGGCGCCUCGGCUACAUCUCAGUAGUGGACACCCUGAAGAUAGUGACCGAAGAGACCAUGACCACAACUACUGUCACAGAGAAGCACAAAAUGAAUGUUCCAGAAACGAUGAAUGAAGUUCUUGAUAUGUCUGAUGAUGAAGUUCGUAAAGCCAAUGCCCCUGAAAUGCUCAGUGAUGGCGAAUAUAUCUCAGAUGUUGAAGAAGGUGAAGAUGCAAUGACCGGGGACACAGACAAAUAUCUUGGGCCACAGGACCUUAAGGAAUUGGGUGAUGAUUCCCUGCCUGCAGAGGGUUACAUGGGCUUUAGUCUCGGAGCGCGUUCUGCCAGCCUCCGCUCCUUCAGUUCGGAUAGGUCUUACACCUUGAACAGAAGCUCCUAUGCACGGGACAGCAUGAUGAUUGAAGAACUCCUUGUGCCAUCCAAAGAGCAGCAUCUAACAUUCACAAGGGAAUUUGAUUCAGAUUCUCUUAGACAUUACAGCUGGGCUGCAGACACCUUAGACAAUGUCAAUCUUGUUUCAAGCCCCAUUCAUUCUGGGUUUCUGGUUAGCUUUAUGGUGGACGCGAGAGGGGGCUCCAUGAGAGGAAGCCGUCAUCACGGGAUGAGAAUCAUCAUUCCUCCACGCAAGUGUACGGCCCCCACUCGAAUCACCUGCCGUUUGGUAAAGAGACAUAAACUGGCCAACCCACCCCCCAUGGUGGAAGGAGAGGGAUUAGCCAGUAGGCUGGUAGAAAUGGGUCCUGCAGGGGCACAAUUUUUAGGCCCUGUCAUAGUGGAAAUCCCUCACUUUGGGUCCAUGAGAGGAAAAGAGAGAGAACUCAUUGUUCUUCGAAGUGAAAAUGGUGAAACUUGGAAGGAGCAUCAGUUUGACAGCAAAAAUGAAGAUUUAACCGAGUUACUUAAUGGCAUGGAUGAAGAACUUGAUAGCCCAGAAGAGUUAGGGAAAAAGCGUAUCUGCAGGAUUAUCACGAAAGAUUUCCCCCAGUAUUUUGCAGUGGUUUCCCGGAUUAAGCAGGAAAGCAACCAGAUUGGUCCUGAAGGUGGAAUUCUGAGCAGCACCACAGUGCCCCUUGUUCAAGCAUCUUUCCCAGAGGGUGCCCUAACUAAAAGAAUUCGAGUGGGCCUCCAGGCCCAGCCUGUUCCAGAUGAAAUUGUGAAAAAGAUCCUUGGAAACAAAGCAACUUUUAGCCCAAUUGUCACUGUGGAACCAAGAAGACGGAAAUUCCAUAAACCAAUCACAAUGACCAUUCCGGUGCCCCCGCCCUCAGGAGAAGGUGUAUCCAAUGGAUACAAAGGGGACACUACACCCAAUCUGCGUCUUCUCUGUAGCAUUACAGGGGGCACUUCGCCUGCUCAGUGGGAAGACAUCACAGGAACAACUCCUUUGACGUUUAUAAAAGAUUGUGUCUCCUUUACAACCAAUGUUUCAGCCAGAUUUUGGCUUGCAGACUGCCAUCAAGUUUUAGAAACUGUGGGGUUAGCCACGCAACUGUACAGAGAAUUGAUAUGUGUUCCAUAUAUGGCCAAGUUUGUUGUUUUUGCCAAAAUGAAUGAUCCCGUAGAAUCUUCCUUGCGAUGUUUCUGCAUGACAGAUGACAAAGUGGACAAAACUUUAGAGCAACAAGAGAAUUUUGAGGAAGUCGCAAGAAGCAAAGAUAUUGAGGUUCUGGAAGGAAAACCUAUUUAUGUUGAUUGUUAUGGAAAUUUGGCCCCACUUACCAAAGGAGGACAGCAACUUGUUUUUAACUUUUAUUCUUUCAAAGAAAAUAGACUGCCAUUUUCCAUCAAGAUUAGAGACACCAGCCAAGAGCCCUGUGGUCGUCUGUCUUUUCUGAAAGAACCAAAGACAACAAAAGGACUGCCUCAAACAGCGGUUUGCAACUUAAAUAUCACUCUGCCAGCACAUAAAAAGGAGACAGAGUCAGAUCAAGAUGAUGAGAUUGAGAAAACAGAUAGACGACAGAGCUUCGCAUCCUUAGCUUUACGUAAGCGCUACAGCUACUUGACUGAGCCUGGAAUGAUUGAACGGAGUACAGGAGCAACAAGAUCCCUCCCCACCACUUACUCAUACAAGCCAUUCUUUUCUACAAGACCAUACCAGUCCUGGACAACAGCUCCGAUUACAGUGCCUGGGCCAGCCAAGUCAGGCUUCACUUCCUUAUCAAGUUCUUCCUCUAAUACGCCAUCAGCUUCUCCGUUAAAAUCAAUAUGGUCUGUUUCGACACCUUCUCCAAUCAAAUCCACAUUAGGCGCGUCAACUACAUCUUCAGUUAAAUCCAUUAGUGACGUGGCAUCUCCAAUUAGAUCCUUUCGGACAAUGUCUUCGCCGAUAAAAACUGUGGUGUCACAAUCUCCAUACAAUAUCCAAGUUUCCUCUGGUACCCUGGCUAGAGCUCCAGCAGUCACGGAAGCUACGCCCUUAAAAGGGCUGGCAUCCAAUUCUACGUUUUCCUCUCGAACCUCUCCAGUGACUACAGCAGGGUCUCUUUUGGAGAGGUCAUCAAUUACUAUGACACCCCCUGCCUCCCCCAAAUCAAACAUUAAUAUGUAUUCCUCAAGUUUGCCAUUUAAGUCAAUUAUUACAUCAGCAGCACCGCUAAUAUCUUCACCUUUAAAGUCAGUGGUGUCUCCAGUUAAAUCAGCAGUUGAUGUCAUUUCAUCAGCCAAAAUUACAAUGGCAUCUUCUCUCUCAUCACCUGUGAAGCAGAUGCCUGGACAUGCAGAGGUAGCAUUAGUCAAUGGAUCUAUUUCCCCUCUAAAAUAUCCAUCAUCCUCAACUUUAAUUAAUGGAUGCAAAGCCACUGCCACGUUACAGGAAAAAAUUUCUUCUGCUACAAACUCUGUGAGCUCUGUGGUCAGUGCAGCCACUGACACAGUUGAGAAAGUGUUUUCUACCACGACUGCAAUGCCAUUUUCCCCACUCAGGUCAUAUGUUUCUGCAGCACCAUCAGCUUUUCAGUCUCUAAGAACUCCUUCCGCAAGUGCACUCUAUACAUCCCUUGGGUCGUCAAUAUCUGCAACUACCUCAUCUGUAACUUCAUCAAUUAUAACAGUGCCAGUAUACUCUGUAGUCAAUGUUUUGCCAGAACCAGCAUUAAAGAAACUUCCAGACUCUAAUUCAUUUACAAAAUCAGCAGCAGCCUUGCUGUCACCCAUUAAAACAUUGACUACGGAGACACAUCCUCAGCCUCACUUCAGUCGAACUUCAUCUCCAGUUAAGUCAUCUUUGUUCCUUGCACCCUCUGCCCUUAAGUUGUCUACACCAUCUUCUUUAUCUUCCAGUCAGGAGAUACUAAAAGAUGUAGCUGAAAUGAAAGAGGACCUAAUGCGGAUGACCGCAAUACUACAGACAGAUGUGCCUGAGGAGAAGCCAUUCCAACCUGAACUCCCAAAGGAAGGGAGAAUAGAUGAUGAAGAACCUUUCAAAAUUGUAGAGAAAGUAAAGGAAGACUUAGUGAAAGUUAGUGAAAUCCUUAAAAAGGAUGUAUGUGUAGAUAAUAAAGGAUCACCCAAAUCACCAAAGAGUGACAAAGGACACUCUCCUGAAGAUGACUGGAUAGAAUUUAGUUCGGAAGAAAUCCGGGAAGCCAGACAACAAGCUGCUGCGAGCCAGUCUCCAUCUCUGCCAGAGAGAGUGCAAGUAAAAGCAAAAGCCGCCUCCGAAAAGGAUUAUAACUUGACCAAAGUUAUUGAUUACCUAACAAAUGAUAUUGGGAGUAGUUCACUGACAAACUUAAAAUACAAGUUUGAGGAUGCAAAGAAGGAUGGUGAGGAGAGACAGAAAAGAGUUUUAAAACCAGCAAUUGCUUUGCAGGAACACAAACUCAAAAUGCCUCCAGCCUCCAUGAGGACUUCCACCUCUGAGAAAGAAUUGUGUAAAAUGGCUGAUUCCUUUUUUGGAACAGAUACUAUUUUAGAGUCUCCUGAUGACUUUUCUCAACACGACCAAGAUAAAAGUCCCUUGUCUGACAGUGGCUUUGAAACAAGAAGUGAAAAGACACCUUCAGCCCCACAAAGCGCUGAAAGCACUGGUCCUAAACCACUUUUUCAUGAAGUUCCCAUCCCUCCUGUCAUUACAGAAACAAGAACUGAAGUGGUUCAUGUUAUCAGGAGCUAUGAUCCCUCAGCUGGGGAUGUUCCCCAGACCCAACCAGAGGAGCCUGUGUCACCUAAACCUUCACCUACUUUUAUGGAAUUGGAACCAAAGCCCACCACCUCUAGUAUUAAAGAAAAGGUUAAAGCAUUUCAAAUGAAAGCCAGUAGUGAAGAAGAUGACCACAAUCGGGUUUUAAGCAAAGGCAUGCGUGUUAAAGAAGAGACUCACAUAACCACAACCACCAGAAUGGUUUAUCAUUCUCCACCAGGCGGUGAAGGUGCAUCUGAAAGAAUUGAAGAAACCAUGUCAGUCCAUGACAUCAUGAAGGCCUUUCAGUCCGGGCGGGAUCCUUCCAAAGAACUGGCAGGUCUGUUUGAACAUAAGUCGGCAGUGUCUCCAGAUGUUCACAAGUCUGCUGCUGAAACCUCAGCCCAGCAUGCAGAGAAGGACAACCAAAUGAAACCCAAACUGGAGCGUAUAAUAGAAGUCCACAUCGAAAAAGGUAACCAAGCUGAGCCCACUGAAGUCAUUAUUAGAGAAACCAAAAAGCAUCCAGAAAAAGAAAUGUAUGUAUAUCAGAAAGACUUAUCCCGGGGAGAUAUUAACCUAAAAGAUUUUCUGCCAGAAAAACACGAUGCUUUUCCUUGUUCAGAGGAACAGGGUCAGCAAGAAGAAGAAGAACUUACUGCUGAAGAGUCAUUGCCUUCUUAUCUGGAGUCUUCCAGAGUAAACACUCCUGUGUCCCAAGAAGAAGAUAGCCGCCCUAGUUCUGCUCAACUCAUAUCUGAUGACUCUUAUAAAACAUUGAAGCUUUUGAGUCAACACUCAAUAGAAUACCAUGACGAUGAGUUGUCAGAACUAAGAGGGGAGUCUUACAGGUUUGCUGAGAAAAUGCUUCUGUCAGAAAAGCUAGAUGUGUCUCAUUCUGAUACUGAGGAAUCGGUUACAGACCAUGCAGGACCCCCUAGCUCAGAGUUACAGGGGUCUGAUAAGCGGUCCAGAGAAAAAAUAGCCACUGCCCCCAAAAAAGAAAUUCUCUCCAAAAUCUAUAAAGAUGUUUCUGAAAAUGGUGUAGGUAAAGUGUCUAAAGAUGAGCAUUUUGAUAAAGUGACAGUGUUGCACUAUUCUGGCAAUGUUAGUAGUCCAAAACAUGCCAUGUGGAUGCGCUUUACUGAGGACAGAUUAGACAGAGGUAGAGAGAAGUUGAUAUAUGAAGAUAGGGUGGACAGGACUGUGAAGGAGGCUGAAGAAAAACUGACUGAAGUGUCACAGUUUUUUCGUGACAAAACUGAAAAGCUAAAUGAUGAACUGCAGUCCCCAGAGAAAAAGGCACGCCCUAAAAAUGGCAAAGAAUAUUCUUCUCAAAGCCCUACCAGUAGCAGCCCUGAGAAAGUGCUACUGACAGAACUGCUGGCAUCCAAUGAUGAGUGGGUUAAGGCAAGACAGCAUGGCCCUGAUGGACAAGGCUUCCCCAAGGCCGAGGAGAAGGCACCCAGUCUGCCCAGCAGCCCAGAGAAGAUGGUUCUCUCCCAACAGACUGAGGACAGCAAGUCCACAGUGGAAGCCAAAGGAAGUAUUUCACAGAGCAAAGCACCAGAUGGGCCCCAGUCUGGAUUCCAGCUCAAACAAUCUAAACUCAGUUCCAUUAGAUUAAAAUUUGAACAAGGCACACACGCAAAAAGUAAGGACAUGUCUCAAGAAGACAGAAAGUCAGAUGGCCAGUCCAGAAUCCCAGUUAAAAAAAUACAGGAGAGCAAGCUACCCGUCUACCAAGUUUUUGCUAGAGAAAAACAGCAGAAGGCCAUAGACCUCCCAGAUGAAAGUGUAUCUGUGCAAAAAGAUUUUAUGGUAUUAAAAACCAAAGAUGAGCAUGCCCAAAGCAACGAAAUUGUUGUAAAUGAUUCUGGCUCUGAUAAUGUGAAAAAACAGAGAACUGAAAUGUCAAGUAAAGCAAUGCCUGACUCUUUUUCUGAGCAGCAGGCUAAAGACUUGGCAUGUCAUAUAACCUCAGAUUUAGCAACUAGGGGACCAUGGGACAAAAAGGUCUUUAGAACAUGGGAGAGUUCGGGAGCCACUAACAAUAAGUCUCAGAAAGAAAAACUUUCGCAUGUACUUGUUCAUGAUGUAAGAGAGAAUCACAUUGGUCACCCUGAGAGUAAAAGUGUUGAUCAAAAGAAUGAAUUUAUGUCUGUGACUGAGAGAGAACGCAAAUUGUUAACAAACGGCUCUCUCUCAGAAAUUAAAGAAAUGACUGUAAAAUCUCCCUCCAAAAAAGUCUUAUAUAGGGAAUAUGUUGUGAAAGAAGGGGACCAUCCAGGCGGAUUGCUUGAUCAGCCUUCCAGGAGGAGCGAGAGCUCAGCAGUGUCACACAUUCCCGUCAGAGUUGCUGAUGAGAGGAGAAUGCUGUCUUCUAAUAUUCCCGAUGGUUUUUGUGAACAGUCGGCAUUUCCAAAACAUGAACUAUCACAAAAAUUGUCCCAGUCAAGCAUGAGUAAAGAGACAGUUGAGACACAGCACUUUAAUUCUAUAGAAGAUGAAAAAGUUACCUAUUCAGAAAUCAGCAAAGUUUCCAAACACCAGAGUUAUGUAGGUUUAUGCCCACCUCUCGAGGAAACCGAAACCUCCCCCACCAAAUCUCCUGAUUCUUUAGAGUUUAGCCCAGGAAAGGAAUCUCCCUCUAGUGAUGUAUUCGACCACAGUCCCAUUGAUGGAUUGGAAAAACUCGCACCACUAGCCCAGACAGAGGGAGGGAAAGAGAUAAAAACUUUACCCGUUUAUGUCAGUUUUGUACAAGUGGGGAAGCAAUAUGAAAAGGAGAUACAACAAGGAGGUGUAAAAAAAAUCAUAAGUCAGGAAUGUAAGACAGUACAAGAAACCAGGGGGACCUUUUAUACAACUAGACAGCAAAAGCAACCUCCUUCUCCCCAAGGUAGUCCAGAAGAUGAUACUCUAGAGCAAGUAUCCUUUCUAGACAGCUCUGGGAAAAGCCCUUUAACCCCAGAAACACCCAGUUCAGAGGAAGUGAGUUAUGAAUUUACAUCUAAGACACCUGACUCGCUCAUAGCUUAUAUACCAGGCAAACCCAGCCCAAUUCCCGAGGUUUCUGAGGAGUCAGAGGAGGAGGAACAGGCCAAGUCAACCUCCCUUAAGCAGACUACAGUGGAGGAAACAGCAGUUGAGCGUGAAAUGCCUAAUGACGUGAGCAAAGACUCUAACCAAAGACCCAAAAAUAACAGAGUUGCCUAUAUUGAAUUUCCCCCUCCUCCACCACUGGAUGCGGACCAGAUUGAGUCAGAUAAGAAGCAUCAUUAUCUCCCAGAAAAAGAGGUUGACAUGAUUGAAGUCAAUCUGCAAGAUGAGCAUGACAAGUACCAGCUGGCUGAACCUGUCAUUAGAGUGCAGCCACCUUCACCAGUUCCUCCCGGGGCAGACGUCAGUGAUUCAAGCGAUGACGAAUCUAUUUAUCAGCCAGUCCCAGUUAAAAAAUAUACCUUCAAAUUAAAGGAAGUGGACGAUGAACAAAAAGAAAAACCCAAAGCUUCUGCUGAAAAGGCUUCCAACCAGAAAGAACUGGAAAGUAAUGGAUCUGGAAAAGAUAAUGAAUUUGGCCUUGGCCUUGAUUCACCUCAGAAUGAAAUUGCCCAGAAUGGGAACAACGACCAGUCCAUCACAGAGUGUUCCAUUGCCACCACAGCAGAGUUUUCUCAUGACACGGAUGCCACAGAGAUCGACUCUCUGGAUGGCUAUGACCUGCAAGAUGAAGAUGAUGGCUUGACAGAGAGUGAUUCUAAACUCCCAAUUCAAGCCAUGGAAAUUAAGAAAGAUAUCUGGAACACAGAGGGCAUUCUGAAGCCAGCUGACCGCUCUUUUAGCCAAAGUAAACUUGAAGUUAUCGAGGAGGAGGGAAAGGUGGGACCAGAUGAGGACAAGCCACCUUCUAAAAGUUCUUCAUCUGAAAAGACUCCUGAUAAGACUGAUCAGAAGUCAGGGGCCCAGUUCUUCACACUGGAAGGCAGACAUCCUGACAGAUCAGUGUUUCCUGAUACUUACUUCAGUUACAAAGUAGAUGAAGAAUUUGCCACUCCUUUUAAAACAGUAGCUACCAAAGGUCUAGAUUUUGACCCUUGGUCUAAUAACCGAGGGGAUGAUGAAGUUUUUGACAGUAAAUCACGGGAAGAUGAAACUAAGCCAUUUGGGCUGGCGGUAGAAGACCGCUCUCCAGCAACAACCCCUGAUACAACGCCAGCCAGAACGCCAACUGAUGAAAGUACCCCAACUAGUGAGCCUAACCCCUUCCCAUUUCAUGAAGGAAAAAUGUUUGAGAUGACUCGCAGUGGUGCAAUUGACAUGAGCAAGAGGGAUUUUGUUGAAGAGAGGCUCCAAUUUUUCCAGAUUGGUGAGCAUACUUCUGAAGGGAAGUCAGGGGACCAGGGGGAAGGGGAUAAAAGUAUGGUCACUGCCACACCACAGCCACAGUCAGGGGACACCACUGUAGAAACCAAUCUAGAGAGAAAUGUAGAGACACCUACAGUGGAACCUAACCCCAGCAUCCCGACCAGCGGAGAGUGUCAGGAAGGCACAUCCAGUAGUGGCUCCCUGGAGAAAUCAGCAGCAGCCACUAACACCUCUAAAGUUGACCCCAAGUUGCGCACGCCUAUAAAAAUGGGAAUUUCUGCAUCCACCAUGACCAUGAAGAAAGAAGGCCCUGGAGAAAUAACAGAUAAGAUAGAAGCGGUGAUGACCAGUUGUCAGGGAUUAGAAAAUGAAACUAUAACAAUGAUUUCAAAUACAGCCAAUAGCCAGAUGGGCGUUAGGCCCCAUGAAAAACAUGAUUUUCAAAAAGAUAACUUUAAUAACAACAACAAUUUGGAUUCUUCCACUAUACAGACAGAUAACAUUAUGAGUAAUAUAGUUCUGACAGAACAUUCUGCACCCACUUGUACCACAGAGAAAGAUAACCCAGUGAAAGUCUCAUCAGGAAAAAAGACAGGGGUACUACAAGGACACUGUGUAAGAGAUAAGCAGAAAGUUCUUGGAGAACAGCAAAAAACAAAGGAAUUGAUAGGGAUUAGGCAAAAAUCCAAACUUCCCAUAAAGGCCACUUCACCAAAAGAUACCUUCCCACCGAACCAUAUGUCAAACACUAAAGCAAGUAAAAUGAAGCAGGUUAGUCAAUCCGAGAAAACCAAAGCCCUUACUACUUCUUCAUGUGUAGAUGUAAAGUCCAGAAUUCCAGUGAAAAACACACACAGGGAUAACAUAAUUGCAGUUAGAAAAGCAUGUGCCACACAAAAGCAAGGGCAGCCAGAGAAAGGCAAGGCCAAACAGCUUCCAUCCAAGUUGCCAGUAAAGGUAAGAUCCACCUGUGUCACUACCACCACCACCACUGCCACCACCACCACCACUACCACCACUACCACCACCACCAGCUGCACAGUUAAAGUUAGGAAAAGUCAGCUCAAGGAAGUAUGUAAACAUUCCAUUGAAUAUUUUAAGGGAAUUAGUGGUGAGACCUUAAAGCUUGUGGACCGCCUCUCUGAAGAAGAAAAAAAGAUGCAGUCCGAGUUGUCCGAUGAGGAAGAAAGUACCUCAAGAAACACGUCGUUGUCCGAGACUUCCCGGGGUGGCCAGCCUUCGGUUACAACGAAGUCUGCUAGAGAUAAGAAAACAGAGGCAGCACCUUUAAAAUCAAAGAGUGAAAAGGCCGGCAGUGAGAAAAGGAGCAGUAGAAGGACUGGUCCACAGAGUCCAUGUGAACGGACAGAUAUCAGGAUGGCAAUAGUAGCCGAUCACCUGGGACUUAGUUGGACAGAACUGGCAAGGGAACUGAAUUUUUCAGUGGAUGAAAUCAAUCAAAUACGUGUGGAAAAUCCAAAUUCUUUAAUUUCUCAGAGCUUCAUGUUAUUAAAAAAAUGGGUUACCAGAGACGGAAAAAAUGCCACAACUGAUGCCUUAACUUCGGUCUUGACAAAAAUUAAUCGAAUAGAUAUAGUGACACUGCUAGAAGGACCAAUAUUUGAUUAUGGAAAUAUUUCAGGCACCAGAAGUUUUGCAGAUGAGAACAAUGUUUUCCAUGACCCUGUUGAUGGUUGGCAGAAUGAGACAUCAAGUGGAAACCUAGAGUCCUGCGCUCAAGCUCGAAGAGUAACUGGUGGGUUACUAGAUCGACUGGAUGACAGCCCUGACCAGUGUAGAGAUUCCAUUACCUCAUAUCUCAAAGGAGAAGCUGGCAAAUUUGAAGCAAAUGGAAGCCAUACAGAAAUCACUCCAGAAGCAAAGACAAAAUCUUACUUUCCAGAAUCCCAAAAUGAUGUAGGAAAACAGAGUACCAAGGAAACUCUGAAACCAAAAAUACAUGGAUCUGGUCAUGUUGAAGAACCAGCAUCACCACUAGCAGCAUAUCAGAAAUCUCUAGAAGAAACCAGCAAGCUUAUAAUAGAAGAGACUAAACCCUGUGUGCCUGUCAGUAUGAAAAAGAUGAGUAGGACUUCUCCAGCAGAUGGCAAGCCAAGGCUUAGCCUCCAUGAAGAAGAGGGGUCCAGUGGGUCUGAGCAAAAGCAGGGAGAAGGUUUUAAGGUGAAAACGAAGAAAGAAAUCCGGCAUGUGGAAAAGAAGAGCCACUCGUAACAGCGAACGGUCAGUCAAGGAUCAUAAGUUUUUACUGCCAGUAUUGAGAAAUUCGUGGAAGAAAUGUCAGCAGGAAGUAAAAAUUCACCGAGAAGUGUGUGUGUGUUCGCUGCUUCCACACAUUAAUGGCAUGAUUUUUUUUAUGCAAAAAGAAAAGAAAAGAAAACCACCCACAUUUUAAUUUAGCAUGAGCCAAUUUACAGAGCAUGGAAAUCACUUUCAUUUCCGGAUUGGCGCGUGUGCAAUUAGCAAUGCAGUGUAUAUACAAGAAGCCAUGCUGUUAACAGUUUAUCUCAAGUAAUUUGGUGUCAUUUACAAAAGGAAGAAAUUCCUGCCAUCAGAAGGGACAGAAGGAGAUGGAAUGAUCAAAUCACAGAGAAACACUAAAAUUACUAAAUCUACAACAGCUCGCCUUAUUUUUCUUGGACCCAAACUGUCAGGGUAUAAACACUAUUUGUUUCUUUUUUAAAACAUCGAUAGUUUUGCUGUAAAUAAUAACACUGUAUAAAUUCUAACAGAAAAAUAGAAUAAAAUGUUGAUAAGGCACUGCCUCUUAGAACACAAACAGAAUAUUGCAAAUGCAUUUAACAAAUAGGGGUCUCAAGUGACUUCACCCUAGAAGAGGAGGGAGGGAUUCUGGGUGGGGGUGACUCUUCACUGAUUCUUGUAUAUUAGCAAUUAUAAUGUUUGUAUAUGCAAAACUGCUAGCUUGAUUUUAAAAAAAAACAAAUCUUUAAAAUCUGCUGCAAAUUUAAAUAAUUCCCAAAAUGAGGAAUUCUGUAGUUCUGUGAAAAAUUUUUUUCUUCAGAAUACUAAUAUUUUGAUGCAUGUGUAUCACCUUAUUUUGAUUAAAUCUUUUCCAAUUUUGCAAACACUACAGUAUACUGCAACACAAAAGAUUUUAUCUGUAAACACAAAGCCCUUCAUCUAAUAUUUGUUGCUAUUGCCAAUUUUUCAAUGAAAUGACCUAAAAACAACAAAAAAAAAUAACCUAUACGGUAGUUGCUUUAGGGGGUGGGGGGAUGCUAUCUGUUAGUGCUUAAAAGGGGGUAAAUGCUUGCCGCUUUAGAGGUGGAUGGUGCUCAUAAAAGGCCCCAGUCGGGGGUAUUUAAAAAGGACUGAACAGAAAUCCUUAGCUAGUAGAAUGGCAGCACGCUGUAAAAUUAUUACUGUAUUGUGUACUGGCUAUAAGAUGUAGACACCUUUCAGUAAGCCAAUCAUUUGUAACCAUUCUAGCAGUGUCAUAUUAGGUUAAUAAGGCUGCUGUGUUUUAAAGGGCAUUUUUAUUUGGGUUUUGGUGAAAUUCUUUAAUUUGUUGAUUAUAUUCACAUAAAAUCAGCAUUCAUUGACACAUAGCUCUAAUGACAUAUGUAUGAAAAACCAUACACUGGAUGACCUAGUCGAUUAUUUAAGCAUAAAAUAAAUUGUGUUAAACUCUUCACCUAUCUGUGCUCUACAGUCUCCUUGUGUUUUCUGGCAAAAGGUAGUUGUCUAAUCCCUUGUCAUAUGAGUCCUGGCCAAUCCACCCCAUUGGUCCUCUUUGUGCCUCUGUGGUCACUGAAGAGAUAAUCUCUAACAUUCAUAUGUGCCCUGCAAGCUCCCAGCUUAUAAAUUCUGUGCAUUUCAUGGGGGAGCCAAGAAUUAAAGAUUAAUUGACAAGUAAGCUUUGCCCACAUCUGUUCAGGCCUUCUUGAAAAGUGAAGAAUUGGAGAUACUAUAGCCAGCAUGUCAAAAAGUUGACUGGCACUUCUAGGAACCAUCAACAUGCAGUUGCUUUUAGCCCACAGAGCUUGUUUUUGUUUUGUUUUAUUAAUUUACAUUUAUUGUCCAUUCUUACAAGUUGGGACAUUUCACAUAAUUAAGUUGCUAACAUCUCUUAAAAAGCAAGAUUUGGCAACAAUGGACCUCAUUCCCAGAAGGUAACAACCUGCUAGAGCCAAGUUGUCCCUGCCCUCUCCAGCCAGGUGUGGGGUCUACAGGUAUCACUGCCACAGCCUCAUUUCUUAUAUUUGUACAACCUGACUGUGAAUUUGCAACCCAUACACUGCGUGAAUCUAAAUUCUACUGAGGCAGAGACCAUGGCUGUUUUAACUUUUAUUCUAGUUACCAGCUUAGCAUAUGGUAGUAGUGAUAGUAGUAACUGUGAUCAUCAUCACUAAAACUGGAGUGCUCACUACAUGCUAUUCUCUGUUCUAAGCACAUUCCAUUUACUUACUUAGUCCUCAUAUCUACUUUAUGAAUUAGGUACUGUCUUUCUUUGAUGGUAAUGAUCCUUUUAUAAAAUUAAAUUAGUGCUAAGAGACUUUCAGCAAUGUUAUAUAUUGCCUGUCCAUUAAAGAUUGUUGCCAAAUGGAGUGAGUUGUCCCCAGUAAGGAUUCACUAUCAAUGCAGAAGAAAUGCACGGAUAAUCUACUUUGCAUAAAGAAUGGGGCUAGGUUGCAUCUGCAUGGUAUCCCAAAUAAAUAAAAUGUGCCACUACCCUUGCACCAAAAUUAUUUUAUGAUGGGUAAAGUUAGACCCUUGAGAGGUUUUUUUUUUAAAAAAAAAAAAAAAAAAAAACUUUCCCAAAAUGCCUCUCUGUAAAGCCAGGAUCAGAAUAUAGGUGUCCUAACUUCCUAUCUAAGAGUUACGAAUUUCUGACUCAGUCUUUGAGAGAAGGUGUUUAUCCUGAACCAGAAACUCAAUGAUGUAUACCUGUUUAGGUAUUAAAUAGUUGUGUUUAUAUGCCCAAAAAUUUGACUUUAGGUAUAUGUGAUAUGCUUUGGUUCCGAUCAAGCAGGAGGUCAUAAGUUUACUCAGAAGUAUCCAAAAUAUGACAUUCAAGAUUUAACUUGCAUAUGUGUGUAUAUGCAUAUAUUUAUACAUGUAUAUGUAGAUUGAAUGUGACAUUAUGUAUUUCUAACAUAAUAUUUGGCCUGCCAGCUUAUAAAUAUGUAUUUAAGCUUUUCAUUGAUUGACAUUACUGUAAAAAAUGAAUUAUGAUUGAGAAGUUCUGGAUAUUUGCUGUUUUUUUCAUUUUAUAUUCUUACUAAAUUAUUGAAUUUGUUAAAUUAAAAUGUGCUAUCACUGUAUUGCCAAAUUAUGGCAAUACACUAUGCAGUAUUAUUUCAAUACUUUAAGAGGCAUCUAUUACUUCAUUGAACACAUAAGCAGCUAGCCUCCUUUCCUCUGUAAAUAAGGACUUUUUGGCAUCCUGAUGUUCCUCGCUGUUCAUUUGGUAUCAUCCUGGAGUUCCAUCAAGACUGAGGAUUUUCUCCAUGGCCAAUAAACUAUUGUCAGCAUCAGCUCACGUUUGGCUGUAUGACAGGGAUAUGUGAGAAGCCCAGAAAUAAAUCACAAAAAUAAUAAGGCAUCUUCUGAGUCUCUCUGAAGAAGCCAGUGAUCCAAAAACUAACUUCAUAUCUGAGUGAGUCUUGGUAUUCUUGAUUUGCUUGAAGAGGCUGUGACAUAUUACAAGGUGUGUAAUUUCCCAGGCAUAUCACACUGCUUCUGUUUCAUGAAUUGAUCAAAUUGUCCAGAAGUAAACAUUUACAAGAUUGAGAUUUGAA